ACCCAGGCUGGAGUGCAGUGCCAUGAUUUCAGCUCACCGCAGCCUCUGCCUCCCAGGUUCAAGCAAUUCUCGUGCCUCAGCCUCCAAAAUAGCUGGGAUUACAGUCGUGUGCCACUAUGCCUGACUAGUUUUUGUAUUUUUAGUAGACACAAGGUUUCACUGUGUUGGCCAGGCUGGUUUUGAUUUCCUGACCUCAGGUGAUCCACCUGCCUUGGCCUCCCAAAGUGCUGGGAUUACAGGCAUGAGCCACUGCACCCAGCCUUCAUCUUUCUUAUUUUUGAAGGAUAUUUUUACCAGAUAUGAAUUUCCCAACUGAUAUAUUUUUUCUUUUAGUUAGCUUCAAAAAUGUUCCAUUAUCUUCUGAACUCUAUUGUAUAUAAUGAUUAGACAGCUAUGAUUCUUAUUGUUCAUUUUAUAUAUACUUUAUUCUCUGUUAUUAAGUUUUUUCUUUAUUUUUGGUCUGUAAUAAUCUGACUAUAAAGUUCUAGAUAUGGUUCCUUUACAUUUAUCAUGCUUCACUUUCCCUUACCUUUGAUCAGUGGGUUGAUUUUUUUAUUGAAUUUGGAGAAAUUUCAACCAUUGUAUCUUCAAAUACUUUUUUCUGCUUCUUUAGUACUUUUCCUCCUCCUAAGACUCCAAUUAUAUGUGUGUUAGACCACUUAUAUGGUGCCACCAGUCACGGAGGUGCAACCCCCAGUCUUUUUACUCUUUGUACUUCAGUUUGGUAAUACCUAUUUACCUGUCUUGAAGUCACUGUUUUUUUUUUCUUUGAUAGUGUCCAAUUAUUGUUAAGCCUAUCCAAUAAAGAUUUCAUUCCACCUACAUUUUAUAGUUAUAGAAUUUACAUUUGGUUUUGUGGGUCUGCUUUUAUUGACUGUAUUUUCUCUAAAUCUUGUGUCAAAUUUUCCUGCUUCUUUACCGGUCUUACAAUUUCUCAUUGUAUACUGGCCAUUGUAGAUGCCAUGUUGUAGUGACUUGGGGAUUUUAUUAUCUUCCUAAUAGUUAAACUGUUCAGGCAAGCAGUUAAAUUAAUAGCAGAUCACAAUGAUCUUUUUAAGAGUUGAUUUUUGAAGGCAGGUACAGUUUGGUUUUAUCCUUAGUCCUGGACAUAAUUCUUACUCUAGGUAGGGCAGUGGUUCUCAAACUGUGGACUGAAGACCCCUGGGAGUUCCCAAGAACCUUUCAGUGGGCCAAACCUUUCACAAAGUGAAAAAUAUUCUCAUAACAAUACUGAGAGGUUUGCCUUUUUCACUGUGGUGACACUUCCACUGGUGGUGUAGAAGCCAUGGUGAAUCUUCUCUGCUUUAGCAUGAGCAAAGGCAGAGGCACCAAAUAGUACUAGUAAUCAUCAUAUUCUUUACCUCCACACACAAAGAAAAUGUGUUAAGAAAAAACCCAUUUUCACUUAAGAACAUCUUGAAGAAGCAGUAUUCAUUUUAUUAAAUCUCAACCCUUGAUUAUAUAUACAUUUAAAAAAUAUUCUAUGUAAUGAAAUGGGAAGUAUCCAUUAAGGUCUUCUGCUGUAUACCAAAGUAUGAUGGUUGCCUUGAAGAAAACCACUUGUACAGUUGUUUAAGUUGUGAGUUAAAGGCCAGGCUCUGUGGCUGAUGCCCGUAAUCCCAGCAUUUUGGGAGGCCAAGGCGGACAGAUCACAAGGUUAAGAGAUCGAGACCAUCCUGGCCAACAUGGUGAAACCCCAUCUCUACUAAAAAUACAAAAAUUAGCUGAGCAUGGUGGCACGCGCCUGUAGUCCCAGCUACUCGGGAGGCUGAGGCAGGAGAAUCGCUUGAACCCGAGAGGCGGAGGUUGCAGUGAGCCAAGAUCGUGCCACUGCAUUCCAGCCUGGUGACAAAGUGAGACUACGUCCCCACCCCCAAAAAAAUUGUGAGUUAAACCAACUGCUUUUUUGACAAAACACCAUAUUUUUCACCAAAGAAUGAAAAACUUUGUUUGUUCAGACUUGGGCAGUAGGAAAACAUUUUCUUGCAAGUGAGCCUGUCACUUCAAAAAUAACUAAUAUUUGUUGCCAAUGAUAUAAUUCAAUCUGUCAUGUUAAAAUUAGAAUUUUGUAAAAUGUUUAUUCAUAAUUUUGAGCUUUAUAGCUUCCUAAUACAUUAAGAUUUUUUAUGAGAUGGGUGGUAAUAUUAACAUGUGAUUUUUUGAUGUUGUAUAGUGAACUACGUCAACAUUUCAAAGAUCUGCAUAACUCUUUGAAUCAGUAUUUUCCAAAUGACCAGUGUAUGAUGUUACAAAAUUACACAUGGAUAAAAGAUUAUUCAAAGUGCAAUGUAACAUAGUAUGAAAAGUUCACAGAUAUGAUUUUAUAUUCCACAUUGUACUUAACCUGCCAGACACUACCAUUUCUUAAGUUUUAGGGUGGUGUCAAAGAAAAAUAUCCACAGUUAUCUGCAUGGACUAGUAAAAUAUUCUGCCAUUUUCCAACUAUGUACCAUGAGAGGCUAGAUUUUCUUCAUAUACUUCAUAUAUAUGAUUUUCUUCAUAUAUUUCAACCUAAAUAACAUAUUGCCAUAGAUUGAAUGCAGAAGCAGAUAUGAGAAUCCAGGUGUCUUUUAUUAAACCAUCCAUUUAAAAGAUUUGAAAAAAUUUAAAACAUCUUUUGUUUUGUUUUAGAAAAGAUUAUUUUUAUAACAAAUCAUUUAUGUUAACAGUUAAUGGUUUAUUGUUAUUUUAAGUGAAUUAGUAAAUAUCUUAAAAUUUCUCUGUUUAAAUUUUUAACAUGACAAAUAUCAAAAUAUAUAACUACAUAAACUAAAAGUCUUUUGGGUCCUCAAUGAUUUUUCUUGACAUUUAAGAAGUUAAACCCAUAUUUAUUUACUGACACUGUAAAACCUUACAUAAAACAUAAGUAGUAAGUAACUAAAAUGUUAAAUCUAAAUCUAUAAUGUUAAAUUAAAAUCUAAGCCUUACAUAGAAAUUAAAAUUCGCUAAACUACUGAUGCUAUGUUGUACAAAACUGUACUCCUUUUAGUUCAUAAUUGGUCACCUCCAUAUUCAGUUGGAAUAUUAGGUUGGUCAGCUUAAAUACUGUGGCUUUGUUUUGGUUAUCCACAGAAUCUUUACACCCAAAUGUUAAUGCAUAAAAAGCAGCAAGACAUUGUUAAAUGAAACAGCAAUAGUGCAGUUUAGACCUGUGACCAACUAUAUAUGAUUAAACUUACUUCCCACAUUCACAUCACAAUAAUCAUCCAUCAUUUAAUAGCUCAACCAAAAUGUUAUACAGUCAUCAACAGGCAAGGCACAUGAAAACCCCGCACAACCAAGAAUGAUUUGGGCCCAAAUGUCAGUAGAUUUGAGUUUGGAAAAACCUUCUUGUAGUUGUUAAGGCUCAAUGGCUCUGGUUAAUUUAAUAUAAUAAACAACAACUUCAUAAUGGAAAAAAAUUAAAUCCUCUAUUGAGGUAUAAAACCUAAUUAAUUUAUAAGGAUAAAGUAAGUGACUACCUUGAAGUCAAAACACAUUAUGGACAAUGAAAGAGUAUUACGAUUGUUCCAAAUUGACAAGGGUAUUUAAACCUAGGUACACAAUCUUUCUUAAAAUUAAUUUAUAGAAAGUCAUAACCUGUGGGUACAUGAAUAUGAAUAUACAUCUUCUCCAACUUGACAAGUACAUUAUUGCUGGGACAGGUACCUUUUAAUAACAAGUAACUUAUUAGCCUAGAAAGGCCAAACUUCUCUUUUUAUUGUCAGCUUUUGGUUUUUAAUAUACCUGGGGUUAUAUAAACAAAAACACAGUCAUAGUAGUUUUGGGCUAAGUAAAUUCUGGAUUAUGUCAAAGAAACCUGAUUGUUUCUAGUAUCUUUUGUAAGCGAAAGAGCAAAUCUUUGUGCUUGCUCAGUGGCCUUUUAGGAAACCUGAAAGGCAGAUUUUAUGUGAAAGACAUAAUCUGUUACAAUCUGUUUCAUUAUUCUGAAUUGGAAAAGGCAUUAACAAAAAGAGUUGUCAGAGGAGCUUUUGACAAGAACAAUAGUUGUGACUAAUUAAUCAGAACAUCAACACAAUAUUUAAAAUAAUGAGAAGGUAGCAAGAUUUUAAUUUUUAUUUAAAUAAAAAAUUCUGUUCUAUUUAAAAAUAGUUUAGAUGUGUAGUAUAAGGUAGCUAAAAGCAUGAAAAUUAUUUGACUCUUAAAAUUUGAAGCAUACACAGAAGUGUGGCAAAAUUAUGCAGAUUUAUUUUCUUCAUGUAUUGAAGAAAAAGAAUAAUACUUUAAUUUCCUCAUAUAGAGUGGACAGUUUACUCCAAGAUCAUCAUUUUCCCUUAGCUAGCAGUCUUUUCUAUCAUAUCAUACUUAUGUCACUUUUUUCAUACAUUAUAUGACAUAGCAUUUCCCAUAUGCAUUUAAACCUGCUAAUAUUGUCAAUAUACCAUGCUGAAUGACACUAUAAUUUAAAGCUUUAUUUUCAAUUUUAAAAUAUAAUUAACAGUAUUAAUGUGUUAUAAGAUGAUGUGUGUAUCACAUUGAUUUUUGACAGGGUAGUUUGAGCUUAGUUGAGUGAAAAUAUGUUUAACAAUGGUCAAGAAAUAAGUAAACUUAAUUGAAAAAUAACUCAAAAUAUUUGUUCUUCCUCUUUUAUGAAUAUCUUCUUAGGAACUUUUUAUGCAACCAGAAAUUAUUUAUUAGUAACUCUCAAGAUCAUUUUGUCUAAGUGAAUUGGAGAUCUUAUAAUUUAAAGUGAUCCUUAAAUAGCAAUACAAUUACUGUUGAUUUUUAAAAUUGAUAGACAUUUAAAAUUUUUAAAUAAGGUAAAAUCUAUAGAGUCACAUAAUUGCAGCAUUAUAUGAAGUUAUAAAAAUCAAUCCUUUUAUAAAAAUUCUGGCUAAUAAAUCUAAGUAAAUGUAAAAUUUAAUUGAACUUUAUAUUUUUACAAUUGUGAACAUUUAUGAAAGCAAUGUUUGCUUUAUCUCAGGGGUUGGAAAACUCUGGCUCUGGAGGCCAAAUCCACCUGUUUUUGCAAAUAAAGUUGUAUUGGAACAUAGUCUUGCCCAUUUGUUUAUAUGUUUACAUAUUGCCCAUGGCUGCCUUGAUAAAAUGGCAGAGUUGCGACCAUUGAGUUGUUAGACAAAAGAGUUGUUAGACAAAACAAAAUCAGCCAAAGCUCAUUAUGAUAAGAAUUUGAUUCCCAUUAAGAUACAUUGGAUGACCACAACUGGGCACAUAAGGGCUUGAUUGAUGGAAGCUGACAUUUGGUUUGAGGGAACAUCAGCGUGGGAAAAUGAGGGACUUGUUGAAGCGACCUCUGUGGAAUCCUCCAGAAAACUAUAAAAUCAGAACAUUCAGAUCACAAGAGCUGCAAAAUCAAGGCUGAGUUUGUUAUUUAACAAGGGAGUGCCUUAAUGCCAAGGAGUGAGUUCAAUUUGGAGUCAAAAACGUAUGAGACCAAAAAAAUAUUUUCAGAAAAUGAUAUUUUUGAAAUAAAUUUUUCCCAGUGGGAGAUGAAGGACAAAAGUAAAACCCUUGGCCUUGAGGCAUCCAUCUUCAGAAAUAAUUGGAAGUGCAAAAGCAUAUUCGAGGGACUAAAAGGACAUCAAGAGGGAUACUUCAGUCAAAUGAUAAUCAGCUAUGAAAAAAUACCUUCUUACAGAAAAAGUAAAUCUCUUACUCCACAUCAAAGAAUUCAUAAUACAGAGAAAUCCUAUGUUUGUAAGGAAUGUGGGAAGGCUUGCAGUCAUGGCUCAAAACUUGUUCAACAUGAGAGAACUCAUACAGCUGAAAAACACUUUGAAUGUAAAGAAUGUGGGAAGAAUUAUUUAAGUGCCUAUCAACUCAAUGUGCAUCAGAGAUUUCAUACUGGUGAGAAACCCUAUGAGUGUAAGGAAUGUGGGAAGACCUUUAGCUGGGGAUCAAGCCUUGUUAAACAUGAGAGAAUUCACACUGGUGAGAAACCCUAUGAAUGUAAAGAAUGUGGGAAGGCCUUUAGUCGUGGCUAUCACCUUACCCAACAUCAGAAAAUUCAUACUGGUGUGAAAUCUUAUAAAUGUAAGGAAUGUGGGAAGGCCUUUUUUUGGGGCUCAAGCCUUGCUAAACAUGAGAUAAUUCAUACAGGUGAGAAACCUUAUAAAUGUAAAGAAUGUGGGAAGGCCUUCAGUCGUGGCUAUCAGCUUACUCAGCAUCAGAAAAUCCAUACUGGUAAGAAACCUUAUGAAUGUAAAAUAUGUGGAAAGGCUUUUUGUUGGGGCUAUCAACUUACUCGACAUCAGAUAUUUCAUACUGGUGAGAAACCCUAUGAAUGCAAGGAAUGUGGGAAGGCUUUUAAUUGCGGAUCAAGUCUUAUUCAACAUGAAAGAAUUCAUACUGGUGAGAAACCUUAUGAAUGUAAAGAAUGUGGAAAGGCCUUUAGUCGUGGCUAUCACCUUUCUCAACAUCAGAAAAUCCAUACUGGUGAGAAACCUUUUGAAUGUAAGGAAUGUGGGAAGGCCUUUAGUUGGGGUUCAAGCCUUGUUAAACAUGAGAGAGUUCAUACUGGUGAGAAAUCCCAUGAAUGUAAAGAAUGCGGAAAGACCUUUUGUAGUGGGUAUCAACUUACUCGACAUCAGGUAUUUCACACUGGUGAGAAACCCUAUGAAUGUAAGGAAUGUGGGAAGGCUUUUAAUUGUGGAUCAAGCCUUGUUCAACAUGAAAGAAUCCAUACAGGGGAGAAACCCUAUGAAUGUAAAGAAUGUGGGAAGGCUUUUAGUCGUGGCUAUCACCUUACUCAACAUCAGAAAAUUCAUACCGGUGAGAAACCUUUCAAAUGUAAGGAAUGUGGGAAGGCCUUCAGUUGGGGUUCAAGCCUAGUUAAGCAUGAGAGAGUCCAUACUAAUGAGAAGUCUUAUGAAUGUAAAGACUGUGGGAAGGCCUUUGGUAGUGGCUAUCAACUUAGUGUUCAUCAGAGAUUUCAUACUGGUGAGAAGCUUUAUCAACGUAAGGAAUUCGGGAAGACCUUUACUUGUGGCUCAAAACUUGUUCAUGAGAGAACUCAUAGUAAUGAUAAACCCUACAAAUAUAACGAAUGUGGGGAAGCCUUUCUGUGGACAACUUACUCAAAUGAGAAAAUUGAUACUGAUGAAACCUUAUGAUUGAAAGUUGUAAAAGAAUAUUUUGUGUGUGUGUAUAGACAACUUAUCAUAAUAAGAACUCUUACUCUUGAGAAACCUUGUGAAUGUAAGGGUUGUGCAAAAGCCAUUCAUUUCUGUUUAUGGGCAAUUAUCUUGCUAUCCAGCAAUUCAUACUAGUGAGAAAUAUUUUGAAUAUAAUUAAUAUGAAAAGGCCUUUAGACUUCUGUACAGUCUUAUUGGAUAUCAAUUUAUACUGAUGUAAAAUCAUUUAAAUGUAAGGAAUGUGUGAAGAUCUUCAUUCAUGACAUAAGGUCUGAUUAACAUCAAAUAAUUGGUAUUUGUUAAAAAGAGUUUAAAUAGGAGGAAUGUGGGAAGGACCUAAACUUAAUUCAGUUCUUGCUGCACAUCAGAGAAUUCAUACUGCUGUGUAAUCCUAUGCACAUAAGGAAUUUGGGAAGGCUUAUAGACACAGUAAAUAUCUUAGAGUACAUCAGAGAAUUCAUCCAAAUGAGAAAUCAUUUGAAUUAGAAUUAUAGGAAGGCCUUUAGACAAAUGCUACCCAAAUUAUUAUCCAGAGACUGGUGCAGUCAUAAAAUUGUCAUCUGUCAAUUGUGAGAUAAACGUGGAAAGUGAGUAAAUAUUUGGAACUUUUAUAGCAAUUUGACAUUUCCAUAACAUUCUGUUUUACAAAAUUAUCAGUCCAUAAAUGAUUGAGAAUUGAAAACAAAGUUUGUUCUUUCCCAGAAAUAAUUUGAGACAAGACUCACACUUUUCAAGACAUGAGACAAGUGACAAUUUAAAUAAGAAAUUCUUCACUUGCACCUCUCUGAUUAGAAUAGCAGAAUAUUCAUACUAUAGCAAGAUUUGGCAAAUGAGGGAAUCAAAAUUUUCUAAUGCCUGUAACAGCAUAAGAUAAUUUAUACCAGAUAUGUUAAAUGUGCAGAAGCCUUCCAACACUAUUCAGUCUUUGUUAAACUUCAGUAAGUUCAUCCUAGAGAGUAACUCUGUUAAUGUAACAAAUGUAGGAAAACCCUUAUCCAUGGCAAAUACCAUACUGUCAUCACCAUUUCACCUCCAUACUACCUGUAGGAUGGUGAGCAAAAUGCUUAUCUCUUCUGGACAUGAUGUUUCAAAUGCUGAUGGUAACUAAUAAUGCUGUUACAGAGAUUAGAUGGAUUUAGUAUGCAUCAUAUCCUUGGAAGAGUAUCUGGUAUGUAGCCUAUGCUUAAUACAUAUUAGCUAUUGUUCAUAUUGUCUUUAUUAUUAGUAUUACUACUGGUGAAUUCUUAGGAGAGGCACAACCGUUUUGAGGAAUGAAUUCAGAAAAGCUUCCCAUAACCACUCAUCCAUUUGAAUUUCAGAUAGUUCAUUCUGGAUAAGAUCUAGUACAGUAUAAAGAAUUUGAGGGGAUUUUAAUUCAGAGUUUAUCCCUUAAGCUGAGCUAAAAAAAUGAGACUUGAAAAAAUCCAGACUUUUGAAGAGUUUAGGAAAGCUGUUUUAUAGAAUGUCACACAUUAGUUUCAUUCCUCAUGGUGAAAUUUGAUAUGGGCCUCUCCUUCACAUUUCUCGUAACAUGAAGUUGGAAAUAGAGGCUUAAACAUUUUUUACCAGAACACUUCAUAGAUGGUGAUGUGUACUUCAUCUUGCAAUACCUCAGAAGCAGAUAGUAUCCAUUUCCCCCAGUAUCACCAGUGCCAAGUUUGAUCACUUAUGGUAACUACUGGAGUUGUCUGUUAUAAAGAUCCAUUAUAUACCUAAUAGGAUUGGUCAGCCUUGAUCAAUGAUCUUUGGAAAUGUGUGAUCAUAUGGUAUGUAUUUUACUUUUUUUUUUUUUUGGGACAGGAUCUCUCUUUCUGUCACCAAGGCUGGAGUGCAGUGGUGUGAUUUCGGCUCACUGCAACCUGCACCUCUCGGGUUCAAGUGAUUCUCGUGCCUCAGCCUCCCAAGUAGCUGGAUACACAGGUGUGCACCACCAUACUGGCUAAUUCUUGUAUUUUUAGUAGAGAUGGGGUUUUGCCAUGUUGGUCCAGGCUGAUCUUGAACUCCUGCACCUGCCUCAGCCUCCCAAAGUGUUGGGAUUACAGGUGUGAGACACUGCGCCUGGCUAUAUUUUACUAUUUGGAAAUCACAAUGCAUCUUAAAAUUGAUGGCUUCUUGCAACCACUUUCAACCAGGUGCCUGUCAUGAUUUAGUGCUAGCAUCAAGGCAGGUUAGUUAUGAAGAAAUAGAGUGUGUGUUUAUAUACUCACACAGUUAGAAAUCGACCCUUUUAAAAAUUAUUUCUUUUUGAAAAUAAUGUCAGUUCCAUCAGAACUAAUGCAUUGAUAACUAAAUGUCUGUGGUUCCUUGUCAUAGGUCUACACCUGACCUCUCUAUUUUGUGCACAUAGGGGAUUCGUAAUAUCACUGUUCAGUCAGUCAUUCACCAUCUAGUGAUCAUCAUUCUACAUGAUUGCACUUUUUCAAAGGCAUAAAAAGCCAACAGUUGCACUCUUAAUAAUCAACUGUAACACAAAGCAGAGUACUUUGGGAGUUUUAACAGGAUAUAUUAUUGGUAACUGGCUAUUAUGCCACUCCCUCUGGGUGCCACAUUUGCCUGUUAACCAAGAAAUGUAGACAUGGUGCCUUAUCCCAACAUUUCUGAAAUUAUAUCUCAAGGAAUCACCAGUGCUUACUAGUACUUGACAAUGAAGGAGGAUUUUACAGUUAAAGAAGCUUAUAAAGUAGCAUCUACUAAAUCCCCUCCUAAGGAACAAGCAAAAGCACCUCACCAGCUUAUCAAAAGACUAAAGAGAAGUGAAAAAAAAAAAAAGACGGCCGGGCGCGGUGGCUCAUGCCUGUAAUCCCAGAACUUUGGGAAGCCGAGGCGGGCGGAUCACGAGGUCAGGAGAUCAAGACCAUCCUGGCUAACACGGUGAAACCCCGUCUCUACUAAAAAUAGAAAAAAUUAGCCGGGCGUGGUGGCGGGCGCCUGUGGUCCCAGCUACUCGGGGAGGCUGAGGCAGGAGAAUGGCGUGAACCCGGGAGGCAGAGCUUGCAGUGAGCCGAGAUUGCGCCACUGCACUCCAGCCUGGGCGACAGAGCGAGACUCCGUCUCAAAAAAAUAAAAAUAAAAAAAGACUAAGGAGUAUUCUAGUGAAGAAAAUGGUUGAACUUUGUUUAAACUGGUGUAUGGCAAACUUCACUGUUGAAAUACUUAUUCCCAUGACCUAUUAUCUUUGUAGGUGGGUGAAAUUGCAUUGGGAACUGCUGCUAUAACCAAAAGAGAAUUUCAGUCACCAUGUCUGGUUGUUAGCUAUGAUGGAAUGGCAGCAUCAUGGUCUCAGUUAUGAGUGAAAAUCUUUGUUGUAGCUAAGUAGUGGUGCCUCCUGAGUUUUAUUAAAUGCCGUUUCACUAUC